GCUUCUCCUCCAGGCACAAUGGCUGAGGAAUGCCCCAGAGCGUGCGCGGAGCCUGUGGCGCCCAAGGCCACGGCCCCGCCGGAGAGGACCAGCGACUACUACCGCGUGAGCGCGGACCUGCCGGGCAGGUUCAACAACCCGGGGUGGUUCCGGGGCUACAGGACCCAGAAGGCUGUCUCCGUGUACAGGACCAGUAACCAGGCUUACGGGAGCAGAGCCCCCACCGUGCACGAGAUGCCUAAAGUAUUUUAUCCAAAUUCGAAUAAAUUUUCCCAACAACUUGCAGCGGGUGGAAUGUUCCGGAACAAUACUCUCAAUGUUUACCUGGAGAAAAGCAUCGUGACUGGCCCCGAUAACUGCAUCACCUCCUGUGACCGGCUCAACUUCCACCCCAGUUACAACAUCAACAGGCCAUCCAUCUGCGAUUGAGGGGCUGGAAACUCCCUCUAGGAGUCCUCUGACCCCAGGGCCUCCUGGAAAAUCAUCAUCCCUCAUCACCCACAGUCGCCCGAUUGUGACGGCACAGACUGCGCUGCCUUCCCUGAAAAUAUUAUUCGUCUGCGGAGUAGGAAAAUAUGCAAACGGGGCCGUGAAGUCCUGCCAUUUCACAUCUAAUAAGUACAUGGGAAAGAUGCUAAUGGUUGACUUUGCAUUAAAAACGUUGUCACAUCCUGA